GUGUUCAGCUGACAGCUGCUGAUAAGGUGGCGGCGGCGAAGGCAGCGGCAGGUCGGGAGCAAGAUGGCGCUGCGGCCAGGAGCUGGUUCUGGUGGCGGCGGGGCCGCGGGAGCUGGCGCGGGGUCCGCCGGGGGAGGCGGCUUCAUGUUUCCUGUUGCAGGUGGGAUAAGACCCCCUCAAGCAGGCCUGAUGCCGAUGCAGCAACAAGGAUUUCCUAUGGUCUCUGUCAUGCAGCCUAAUAUGCAAGGCAUUAUGGGAAUGAAUUACAGCUCUCAGAUGUCCCAAGGACCUAUUGCUAUGCAGGCAGGAAUACCAAUGGGACCAAUGCCAGCAGCGGGAAUGCCUUACCUAGGACAAGCACCCUUCCUGGGCAUGCGUCCUCCAGGCCCACAGUACACUCCAGACAUGCAGAAGCAGUUUGCCGAAGAGCAGCAGAAACGAUUUGAACAGCAGCAAAAACUCUUAGAAGAAGAAAGAAAAAGACGCCAGUUUGAAGAGCAGAAGCAAAAGCUCAGACUUUUGAGCAGUGUGAAACCCAAGACAGGAGAGAAGAGUAGAGAUGAUGCUUUGGAAGCCAUAAAAGGAAAUUUAGAUGGGUUUUCCAGAGAUGCAAAAAUGCACCCUACUCCAGCAUCGCACCCCAAGAAACCAGAUUGCCCCACAUCAUCUCAUUCUACUAAAACUGUCUCCCCAUCACCUGCCUUUCUUGAUGAAGAAGAAUUCAGUGACUUUAUGCAGGGGCCUGUUGAAGUUCCCCCAUGUGGGCCUUCUUCCACGUCCCAGCCCUUUCAGUCUUUCCACCCCUCCACCCCACUUGGCCAGUUGCAUACACAGAAGGCUGGGACACAGCCUCUCCCUCCAAGUCAGAGUCCAGUGCCUUUUGCCUUACAUGGCGUCCCUGGGCAAAUUCCUUACUUCUCUACUGCUUCAGCCUCACACAGUGUACCAGAAGCAGGCCCUUCCUUGGAGGAGAAGUUCCUAGUAUCUUGUGAUAUAAGUACAUCUGGGCAGGAACAAAUUAAAUUAAAUACUUCUGAAGUUGGCCACAAAGCCCUAGGCCCAGGUUCCAGUAAGAAGUAUCCCAGUUUAAUGGCCAGUAACGGGGUUGCUGUAGAUGGAUGUGUAAGUGGUACCACCACUGCAGAGGCAGAAAAUACUUCAGAUCAAAACCUGUCAAUUGAAGAGAGUGGUGUGGGAGUAUUUCCCUCACAGGAUCCUGCUCAGCCCAGAAUGCCUCCUUGGAUUUACAAUGAGAGUUUGGUUCCAGAUGCCUAUAAGAAAAUCUUAGAAACCACAAUGACUCCAACUGGAAUAGAUACUGCCAAACUGUAUCCCAUUCUGAUGUCAUCUGGGCUUCCCAGGGAAACUCUUGGACAGAUAUGGGCCUUAGCUAAUCGAACUACACCUGGCAAACUUACAAAAGAAGAACUUUAUACCGUUCUAGCCAUGAUAGCGGUAACACAGAGGGGCGUUCCUGCAAUGAGUCCUGAUGCUUUAAACCAGUUCCCAGCAGCUCCUAUUCCAACUUUAAGUGGCUUUUCUAUGACUCUGCCUACACCGGUGAGUCAGCCAACUGUGAUACCUUCAGGUCCUGCGGGCUCCAUGCCCCUCAGCCUUGGACAGCCAGUCAUGGGCAUUAACCUUGUUGGACCAGUGGGUGGAGCUGCAGCCCAGGCUUCUAGUGGUUUCAUACCAACCUACCCUGCAAAUCAGGUAGUAAAGCCAGAAGAAGAUGACUUCCAGGAUUUUCAAGAUGCUUCUAAGUCAGGAUCCCUUGAUGACUCAUUCAGUGAUUUCCAAGAGUUGCCUGCUUCUUCAAAAACAAGUAACUCCCAGCAUGGAAACAGUGCCCCUUCUUUGUUGAUGCCACUUCCUGGAACUAAAGCAUUGCCUUCAAUGGACAAAUAUGCUGUGUUUAAAGGAAUUGCAGCUGACAAGUCCUCUGAAAAUACUGUUCCACCUGGAGAUCCUGGUGAUAAAUAUAGUGCUUUCAGAGAACUUGAACAGACAGCAGAGAAUAAACCUUUAGGAGAAAGCUUUGCAGAAUUCAGAUCUGCAGGAACUGAUGAUGGUUUCACCGAUUUUAAAACAGCCGAUAGUGUAUCACCACUAGAGCCACCAACAAAAGACAAAACUUUUCCACCAUCCUUCCCCUCAGGAACUAUACAACAGAAACAACAAACACAAGUGAAAAACCCUCUGAACUUAGCAGACCUAGAUAUGUUUUCCUCAGUUAAUUGCAGCAGCGAGAAACCAUUGUCUUUUUCAGCUGUGUUUAGCACAUCAAAAUCAGUUUCUACACCACAGUCAACAGGUUCUGCUGCUACUAUGACAGCAUUGGCAGCAACAAAAACUUCUAGUUUGGCUGAUGAUUUUGGAGAAUUCAGCCUUUUUGGGGAAUAUUCUGGUCUAGCACCUGUUGGGGAGCAGGAUGACUUUGCAGAUUUUAUGGCUUUCAGUAAUAGCUCUAUUUCAUCUGAGCAAAAGCCGGAUGACAAAUAUGAUGCCCUUAAAGAGGAAGCCAGUCCUGUUCCUCUAACCAGCAACGUGGGCAGCACAGUGAAGGGUGGACAAAACUCGACUGCUGCGUCUACCAAGUACGAUGUCUUCAGACAACUUUCUCUGGAAGGGUCUGGACUAGGUGUUGAAGACCUGAAAGAUAACACUCCUUCAGGAAAAAGUGAUGAUGAUUUUGCUGACUUCCACUCCAGUAAAUUUUCUUCCAUAAACUCGGACAAAUCCCUGGGAGAGAAAGCAGUGGCUUUCAGACACACCAAAGAAGACUCUGCAUCAGUGAAGUCCUUAGAUCUCCCUUCCAUUGGUGGCAGCAGUGUUGGCAAGGAGGACUCUGAAGAUGCACUCUCUGUUCAGUUUGACAUGAAAUUGGCUGAUGUGGGAGGAGAUCUUAAGCAUGUCAUGUCUGAUAGCUCUUUGGAUUUACCAACAGUUAGUGGCCAGCAUCCUCCUGCUGCAGAUAUAGAGGACUUAAAAUAUGCUGCUUUUGGAAGCUACAGUAGCAAUUUUGCAGUGAGCACACUUACAAGCUAUGACUGGUCAGACAGGGAUGAUGCAACUCAGGGCAGAAAACUCUCUCCAUUUGUCCUCUCAGCAGGAAGUGGAUCCCCCUCAGCCACCUCAAUUCUUCAAAAGAAAGAGACUUCAUUUGGCAGUUCUGAAAACAUCACCAUGACAUCUCUCUCCAAAGUAACGACCUUUGUAAGUGAAGAUGCUCUUCCAGAGACCACCUUCCCAGCUCUUGCCAGUUUUAAAGACACGAUUCCUCAGACCAGUGAGCAAAAGGAAUAUGAAAACAGAGACUAUAAAGAUUUCACAAAACAGGACCUGCCUACGGCUGAACGGAGCCAGGAGGCCACGUGUCCCAGCCCAGCGUCCAGUGGUGCCUCUCAAGAAACCCCGAACGAAUGUUCGGAUGACUUUGGAGAGUUUCAAAGUGAAAAGCCCAAAAUCAGCAAAUUUGACUUCUUAGUAGCCACUUCACAAAGCAAAAUGAAAUCCAGUGAAGAAAUGAUCAAAAGUGAGCUGGCAACCUUUGACCUUUCUGUUCAAGGAUCACACAAGAGGAGUUUGAGCCUUGGUGAUAAAGAAAUAAGCCGUUCUUCUCCUUCUCCAGCUUUGGAGCAGCCUUUCAGAGACCGUUCCAAUACUCUGAAUGAGAAGCCCGCCCUGCCCGUCAUCCGAGACAAGUACAAAGACCUGACGGGAGAGGUGGAGGAAAAUGAGAGAUAUGCAUAUGAAUGGCAGAGAUGCCUGGGGAGUGCCCUGAAUGUCAUUAAGAAGGCAAAUGAUACCUUAAAUGGAAUCAGUAGUAGUUCUGUUUGCACAGAAGUAAUUCAGUCAGCUCAAGGCAUGGAAUAUUUAUUAGGUGUUGUUGAAGUGUACAGGGUAACCAAGCGUGUGGAGCUGGGGAUAAAAGCCACUGCAGUGUGCAGUGAGAAACUCCAGCAGUUGCUGAAGGACAUCGAUAAAGUAUGGAAUAACCUAAUCGGCUUCAUGUCACUCGCCACACUCACAUGCUGCUGGGAAAAGAUGACUGUGAUUACAAAGCAUCUCUCUCCUUACCAUGAGCUCUUAGAAGAAAAGCCAGAUGAAAACUCGCUGGAUUUUUCCUCCUGUAUGUUACGGCCUGGGAUUAAAAAUGCUCAGGAGCUUGCCUGUGGAGUGUGCCUCUUGAAUGUGGACUCGAGGAGCCGGAAAGAAGAGAAGCCUGCAGAAGAACAUCCUAAAAAAGCAUUCAACUCAGAAACAGACAGUUUCAAGCUGGCCUAUGGAGGGCACCAGUAUCACGCCAGCUGUGCCAACUUCUGGAUCAACUGUGUCGAACCAAAGCCUCCUGGCCUCGUCCUGCCUGACCUGCUCUGAACAACUCCUCUGUGAAGCAUUGACUUUUUUUUUUCUGUGACACCCCACGGGGUGACAGGGACCAAUAAAUAGAAUGCGAGCACUGCACAGUUCGCUUCCCUGAAUCGAUAUGAAGAACACCGCAAGGGACGGGGCCCCCGUCAUCCCCACGGCCAGUCUGCAGGACUUCAGGUAAAAUUGUCCCACCCAAACUGCACGUGGCACCAGAAGCUUGCUCACUUAUCUCUACUUAAGAUUUUCUGAAAUACGGACCACGGCUUUCUUGAUCUAAGGAAGAACUUGCUGCUGCAGUAUUGAAACUGUGAAGAACUGACAUUUGAAGAAAAAUAGAUUACCGUUGCGGGACUAGAAUGGGCGACUGCUUGGAGCCAGUGCUUGUUUUUAUCUAGGACACUUACUGUCCUGUGAAGUAGAAUACAUUUAUCUGCAUUUAGUUUGUUAAUGUCUGAAAUGAAUAAAAAGAGGAAAUUGCGAUUAAACUGAUGUUCUGCUUUUUAUGGAGAAGAUUCUGCCCAUCUCCCCUGGACAGUAGCAGGCAGGUGAGGGCAGAUUUUACCCACUUGGUUGUCACAACUGAACCAGUUCUCUACUCCUUCCCUUCACUUCUGUCCACUCUCAAGACUUUUUCCCAAAACAUGCCUGGGCACUCUGCAGCCGUGAAGAAUGCUCAUUUUGACAGAGGCCCAAAUCCUGUGUAUUAGGAUAAUAUCCUUCCCCCCGGGAGCCUUCGCUGCAAACCUGUUCUGCCGCAUGCAAAGACUGUGACCAUGGAGUUUUCUCAGACAAGAUUUGGAAAGGCAGUGGAAUGAAAUCUCUUUGCAGUGGCCUCUCUCCAAAUUUCCAAAGAUGACUGCAUAGGGACCAACACUGCCUGACUUUGCAGUAUCUGUGAGAAAAACCUGAAAAUUAAUUCAGGGUGAAAAUGUGGAGCUCUCGGCCUAGUGUAAAGUAUCAAGAUGUAUAUUUAUGGGAUAGAUACAUGACUUAGAAGAAGUAGAAGAAAAUUGUCCAGAAACAGUACUGAAUUUUAGAUAGAAAAGGCUCAUGCUUCCUGGAGUAGGGAAUUGUCUUUGCCAUUUAAUGUGAAUGCAUAAAAUUAGGGGAAAAACCCAAGUGGCUAAGAGCUGUGUUAUUCCUGGGAAGAACUACCAAUCUAGGGCACACGUCUCUCUGAAUUGUUGAUUAUGCGCUUUAUGAAGAGAUUUUUCAAUCUCGUGUGCUUUACUUUGUGUGGUUUAGACCCUCUGACCUAGACUUUUAUUUUUAAACUGAAAAAGUUGGUCUUGUCUAUAUAAUUGCUGCUUUUACAUAAUUUAUUUUCCCCUCUCAGGACAAAUUCUGUCUUGCUCCAUCUUACAGCUUUUCCAUGUUCUCCAAGAAAGGUGUGGAACAUUUUCAUUAAACAGCUGUUGCUGAGGCUUCUGCUUGACCUUCUGCGUGCCCGAAUGCACAGAGAGGCACCGAGGAGAGAAAGGCUUUUCUCACUCGCUCCCGAUGAUACCGUCUCUGGCCAUUCCUGACUGAGGCAGCUCACUCUGAAUGGGCACCUUUGGAGCUUUUGCCCACCACAAGGCUAGUGGGGUGUUUCUAACAACACAAGUGGGACAGCUUUUGGCAGGCUUUUCCUGAGGCCUCGGCGCUUCCAUCCUGGACAGCACCACUUCCACAUGGAGCUGGAAUGCAAGCAGGCUGCUAAUUGGCCUUAAAAAUUCUUUGUUUUUUUUUGAGAUGGAGUUUCACUCUUGUUGCCCAGGCUUGAGUGCAAUGGCACAAUCUCAGCUCAGUGCAACCUCCGCCUCCCGGGUUCAAGCGAUUCUCCUGCCUCAGCCUCGUGAGUAGCUGGGAUUACAGGCGUGCACCACCACGCCCAGCUAAUUUUGUAUUUUUAGUAGAGGCAAGGUUUCUCCAUGUUGGCCAGGCUUGAACUCCGGACCUCAGGCGAUCCGCCCGCCUCAGCCUCCCAAAGUACCGGGAUUACAGGCGUGAGCCACUGCGCCUGGCCUAAAUUUCAUAACAGAACCAUGACAGCAGAAUCUACCUUUGCAAUAAGAAUGUUUCCCAGGAGUUAGAGACCAGCCCUGGGCAUGAUGGUAAAGACCCCAGCUAAUUAUACAAAAAAUAAUUAGCCGGGUAGGUGGAGUGCAUCUGUGGACAUUCGUGGUCCCAGCUACUAGGUAAGCUGAGGCGGGAGAUCACAAGUCCAGGAGUUUGAGGCUGCACGUGACAGCGUAGGUGAUGACAGAGCGAGACACUGUCUCUUAAAAAAAAAAAAAAAAAAGUUUCCCAGUUUGAAUUUGUAUUGCUGAAGCAUUUUUUUGAAAUGCUAUAUAGAUGCCUGUCAUGUCACAGUGGCCCAGUAUCAACAUUUUAAAAAGCUCACUUGGUAGCUGGGCUGGUUUCUAUUCCUGAGAAAUUCCAGAAUGCCUCAGAUAAAAUUCCUUAGUAUAAUCCCCAUUUUCCUUACCAAGGAUGGUAGGCUUAGUCACUCCUUGGGAGGUGCCACAGGAAAAUUCAGCAGAUGUCAACAGAAAAAAAGCCUUUGCUAUGAAAAGUAUUCACUACCUUUCAUAUCUCUUGAAUACUUGAAAUGUUUAAUUAGAUGCCACCAAUAGGGAUCCAAGGAGUGUGGGACACGGUUGCGCUGCUUUUCUUUAUAAACGUUUAUUAAAAUGGCUCAACGCUGCAUUCAGCUUCACCUCAGCUCUUCUUGUCAGCCAGGAGCCCCGUGUCCUUGGAAACUGUAGCCAAGGUUACUUAUUUCCAUACUGUGCAUUGUGUCAGCCCGCUUCACCCCACUGCUUGAAUGGCCAUUAAUAAGCACUUUUCUUUUUUUGGUGGGAUGUUUUGCCUUUAAAAUUUUUAUGGCUUAGUGUGUAAUUUAAUUUUUGUCUGGACAUGCUUGAGAUAGAAGAGGUACUGGAUAUAUGAGGAUAUUUUCCAUGCUUUAUUUUUCCUGUGGCUACUAGUUAGCAUUCCAUAGGGGUUGUGAAUUUUUAAUUAUUUGAAUAUUUUGUGUACAUAUACAUAUUUGAAGGGUUUUGGGGGGGUCUUAUUUGUUUAAAGGUGUCUUCUGUUUGCCUAUUUCAAGUGUACUUCAGCUUUGCAAAGAUUAUAGGGCUGUAUGUUACAGAAAUAGGAAAUGCUGGCCCUGUACUGGGGACCACUACAAAAAUUCCCUUUAGCCGGGCGUGGUGGCUCACGCCUGUAAUCCCCAGCACUUUGGGAGGCCGAGCCGGGUGGAUCACCCGAGGUCAGGAGUUCAAGACCAGCCUGGCCAACAUGGCGAGACCCUGUCUCUACUAAAAAUACAAAAAUUAGCUGGGCAUGGUGGCAGGUGCCUGUAAUCCGAGCUACUCGGGAGGCUGAGGCAGGAGAAUUGCUUGAACCAGAGAGGCGGAGGUUGCAGUGAGCCGAGAUCGCGCCACUGCACUCCAGCCUGGGCAACAAGAGCGAAACUCUGUCUCAAAAAUAAAAAAUUCCCUUUAACACCUUCAAGGUCAAAUGCCUGCCUUUGUGAACAGUUAAUAAACUGACAUUUUCAGACAUUUGCCAUUCAGAAGGGAGCAUUGUAGCCUGCUGUAGACCAUUCCAGCAAAUGUCAGAAUGCAGGGCAAGAUGUGUGUCGACUAUGUUUUUUAUGUUUAAGUUACUUACUUAUUUCUUCAGGUAAGUGUGUACCAAAUAACAAUACUGAAAAGCCCUCCCCUUGCCAGGCCGAGGAAAUAAAGCUUAAGUGAAACAGCUCUUGGGGGAAAAAUGCCACUUUACAAAUACUUUUCUAACAAAAUAGCAUUAUAAUGAAGUUUUUACUUAAUUCCAUUAUUUAUAUGUUGACGUGAAUGUAAGUGGUUAAAAAGUAUUCAUGUGGGACAUCUCAUUACUUUGUAGCUGUGGCUUUAUUAACCAGUGAAUGCUGUGGCCCUUAGCGAAAUGCGUUGUCUUCUGCGUGAUGUGGAAUUCGCGCCUGUAUUUUAAAAGAUGGUGUGGUUUCUCCCUUGUUUGUAUUUUAAUAAACAACUGCUCUAAUUGAUGUGUUUAGACAUUAUAAAGCUUUACCUUUAAAAUAUUUUCAGGGUCUGUUCUGAAAUCACCCCUUGUUAAACUUCUCUAACCAAAAUACAAGUGUAGAAGAA